GGAGGCCACGCUUGCAGAGCUGGAGCGCGCGUCUAUCGCCCCAGAACCCCCCUCCCUGCCCUAUCCUCCGCCACCCCUUCUGUUGCGGGGCGCGCGCCAGCCUGGGUGUCUGUAUGCGCUCGAGGCGGGGGCGCGGGUUGCGGACGGAGGCGCGGGAGGCGGUUCUGCGCGGCGGGGGCCGUACCCGCGGCGGAGCGAGGAGGCGAGAAUGGAUCAAUGGUGCCACGGAGCACAUCGCUGACGCUGAUUGUGUUCCUUUUCCACAGAUUGUCUAAAGCCCCAGGAAAAAUGGUGGAAAAUUCACCGUCGCCAUUGCCAGAAAGAGCGAUUUAUGGCUUUGUUCUUUUCUUAAGCUCCCAAUUUGGCUUCAUACUUUACCUCGUGUGGGCCUUUAUUCCUGAAUCUUGGCUAAACUCUUUAGGUUUAACCUAUUGGCCUCAAAAAUAUUGGGCAGUUGCAUUACCUGUCUACCUCCUUAUUGCUAUAGUAAUUGGCUACGUGCUCUUGUUUGGGAUUAACAUGAUGAGUACCUCUCCACUCGACUCCAUCCAUACAAUCACAGAUAACUAUGCAAAAAAUCAACAGCAGAAGAAAUACCAAGAGGAGGCCAUUCCAGCCUUAAGAGAUAUUUCUAUUAGUGAAGUAAACCAAAUGUUCUUUCUUGCAGCCAAAGAACUUUACACCAAAAACUGAACUGUGUGUAACCAUAGUAACACCAAGCACGUAUUUAUUUAUAAGUUUUUGCCAUUAUAAUUUUGACCAUAAAUUAAUUUGACCAUCUCUCUUAUUAAUAGAGAAGUAAAAAAUGUAAGUUGACCUUCUCUUAGAUUAUGUUCAAUGAAUAUUGUAAAUGUUCAAGUAUUGUUAAUGAAUAGAAUAAAUACAAUAUUGCAUUCCCAUAUAGCAGACUU